AUAAAACAUCUGGAAGUUUCCAGGGGGCUGCUUUGCAUCUGAAACUGUCAGCCCCAGAAUGUUGACAGUCGCUCUCCUAGCCCUUCUCUGUGCCUCAGCCUCUGGCAAUGCCAUUCAGGCCAGGUCUUCCUCCUAUAGUGGAGAGUAUGGAGGUGGUGGUGGAAAGCGAUUCUCUCAUUCUGGCAACCAGUUGGACGGCCCCAUCACCGCCCUCCGGGUCCGAGUCAACACAUACUACAUCGUAGGUCUUCAGGUGCGCUAUGGCAAGGUGUGGAGCGACUAUGUGGGUGGUCGCAACGGAGACCUGGAGGAGAUCUUUCUGCACCCUGGGGAAUCAGUGAUCCAGGUUUCUGGGAAGUACAAGUGGUACCUGAAGAAGCUGGUAUUUGUGACAGACAAGGGCCGCUAUCUGUCUUUUGGGAAAGACAGUGGCACAAGUUUCAAUGCCGUCCCCUUGCACCCCAACACCGUGCUCCGCUUCAUCAGUGGCCGGUCUGGUUCUCUCAUCGAUGCCAUUGGCCUGCACUGGGAUGUUUACCCCAGUAGCUGCAGCAGAUGCUGAGCCUCCUCUCCUUGGCAGGGGCACUGUGAUGAGGAGUAAGAACUCCCUUAUCACUAACCCCCAUCCAAAUGGCUCAAUAAAAAAAAUAUGGUUAAGGCUAGUCUGUGUGGGGGCAUCUGUGGCUGGGAUAUCUGCCUCCUGACUUAGCCGGGGACGUGCAAAUCUCACUUCUGGCUGGCUUUGGACAUCUGUCUGGAAGAUGGGAAGAUGAGGGAGAGGUAUGUAAGAAUCCUGGGCUUUGUGCUAUAAUUUAUCAAGAGGAGAUGAGAUUCUGGCUUGCAUCAACGCUCUUCAAGGACAGCUCCUUGGAACAUUGAUCCAAACUGGAGUCAUGGGUCUGAGGGCAAGGCCUAGUUGUGGCUUACACCAAAACCCCAGAUGUCCCACUCUCCAGCUCUCCUCACCCCUGGUCCUCCCCUUGAGAAAGUGGUGAACUCACUUGCUGUGUGUGGGUGGCCAGGACCAUUAGCCUUUGUUCUUUCCCAGAACCCACCUGACUCCUGAAACUUAGCUGAAGUCUGUGCCCGAGGACCCUGCCCUGUUACCAGGCCCAGUUCCUCCUCACCUCUACCCAUGAGCCCCGGUGUCCUGCUAAGCCCUCUCAGAUCUGGGAUUCCUCCUUCCUCAGGAAGCCACCACCUUCUCAGCAGUGGAAACCCUGCCCACACUAUGCUCUUAGGCUUUAGCCAUCAGAAGGUUACAGUGGACUGCGGGAGGCUGACACUAGGCUGAACUCAUUAAGGAAUGAAUGGGAGGUGAGAAGACACAGGCAGCAAGAAUCGAGUGUUUCAAGAAGUUUGGCUGUGGUUUGCCAGAAAUAGGCAAGUCAGUUUUCGGGGGUGUAAGGAAAAAGGGUUUUGUGUCUUUUUAAAAUCCUAGACAGGAGAGUCACAAGCAUGUUCACAUGAUAAAGAGGAAGAAAGAGAAAGAGGCUGGAGAUUCUGAAAAGAGAUCACUGGUGAGGUCUCAAAAGAGAUAGAAGAGGAUGGUUAUGUAGUUGGGGAAAGAAAUUUUAAGAAGGGAAGAAAAUUAAAAUGAGUGAAGGUAUACGUUAGUUUUGUAAAAGUUAUCAAUAUCUGGCUGGGCACAGUGCUCACACCUGUAAUCCCAGCACUUUGGGAGGCCAAGGCAGGCAGAUCAUUUGAGGUCAGGAGUUGGAGACAAGCCUCCAACAUGGUAAAACCCUGUCUCUACUAAAAAUACAAAAAUUAGCCAGGUGUGGUGGCAGUCACCUGUAAUCCCAGCUACUUGGGAGGCUGAGGCAUGAGAAUCACUUGAAUGCUGGAGGCAGAGGUUACAAUGAGUUGAGACAGCACAACUGCACCCCAGCCUGGAUGACAGAGUGAGACUCCAUCUAAAAAAAAAAGGAAUGUUAUCAGUAUCAAAAUGGAGUAACAUAUGUCACAUCCUAACAAAAUGGAACCAACCUGACACCUAAAUUAAGCAUUGCACCUGAUAACACCAUGGAGGACUGGGUGGAGAAUCAGCAGACAAUGGCAGGGAGAGGCAGUCUGUGGACCAAGUUCAGGUGAAAGGAUCACCCAUCAUGUUGGGCAUCAGAUCAGGCAGGUUCACACACUACCUGAGGAAGCUGGUCUUUGUGACAGACAAGAGCUGCUCUGCCUCUUGGGAAACACAGGCACCAGUUUUAGUGCCAUCUUCUUGCACCCAAAUGCUGUCCUUUAACUCAUCAGUUACAGUGCUGGAUCCCUCAUCACUGCCAAUACGGGGCUAGCAAUAUGUCUGCCCCAGUGAAUGCAGCCGCCACGGAGCCCCAGCCUCCUCUAUGGCAGGGGCCCUGUGGUGGGGAAUGAGGACUUCUCUAUCAUUAACCUCCAUGCAGUUGGCUCAAGAAAAGGAUAUGGUAGUUGGGCAAGGGGGCUCACACCUGUAAUCCCAGCACACUUGUAAUCCCAGGAGGGUCGCUUGAGCCCAGGAGUUUAAGGCCAGCCCGGGCAACAUAGCAACCUGUUUGUAGGCAAAAUGAGGAGUUGAAGUUCCCCGUAGGAUCUUCUAGGGCUCAACCAGCCUUCAUGUGCAGUGGGACUGGCAAGAAAUCUGUCAUCCCUGUUACCACUUUGAAGGUCUCAGUGUGUAUGCAGGUCCUGAAAAGUUCAAGUCCCACCUGAAACGCAACACAGCAUCAUGCUCUGAUUCAUCAGUGAUUCCCUAAUCAAUGCCAUUGGCUUGCAUUGGGACUAUCUAUCCCAGCCUAUCCAGUGACUUCAGCAGCUGCAGAGCCCCAGCCUCUUCUUUGGCAGGGGCACUGUGGUGAGGAGGAAGGAUUCCCUUAUCACAAAUCUCCAUCCAAUUGGUUCUAUAAACAGAUAUGGUGGCCCAACUGUUGCGGGAAGUCAGGGACCCCGAACGGAGGGACUGGCUGGAGCCACAGCUGAGGAACAUAAAUUGUGAAGAUUUCAUGGACAUUUACCAGUUCCCAAAAUUAAUACUUUUAUACUUUCUUAUGCCUGUCUUUACUGCAAUCACUAAACAUAAAUUGUGAAGAUUUCAUGAACAUUUAUCAGUUCCCAAAUAAUACUCUUAUAAUUUCUUA